ACUGGCAGAUCUUUGCUGAGGAGCAGUCAGCAUCUUGCUGUCCUGGAUGCCUUGCUGAGUGGUAUACUUACAGUGGGGGAAUAUACAGGUGUUGGGAGCAAGCUUUUGGUUUAGGCUCCACCGUCAGACUCAUUAAGCUGUUAUUGGCCUAGGCAGAGUGGGUGGUAUUUGCAGAAGCUGCGGUGUUCCGGAUGAUCAGACACCACUGUUUGUUUGUUUUUUUAAAUAUGUAAUCUGAAUCCAGAACCCCUGCCCUCAUUCUGUCACUUUAUAGGGUUUAAGCAUAGAGCUGGUUGCUGUUCACCUAAUGGAUGCUCAUUAUUUGCUAAGGGAACUAAUGUUAUUGAAUCGAAUGGAUUUGGGGUUAUGAAGGAAAUUGCUCCAUUAAAGCAGCUGUCGAAUUACAUUUAAAUGCAGUGGCUAAAAAAUCGCAGGAUUUGGAAGUUUUUUUUUUUUUUUUUUUUGAGGGGUAGAGGGUUUGUCACAUACGUAACAGGUUUGUUUCACUGGAGUUGAGCUGCAGCUGAGGCCUGUUUGUCUUGUUCAUCUUAGUCUGCUCACCAGUCUCUACUUGCUUGGUCUGAAUAUUUAUAUUCCCCCAAAAUUCAUGUGUUGAAAAUCCUCACUUCCAAGGUGAUAGUAUUGACAGGUGGGGCCUUUGGAAGGUGAUUAGGUCAUGAGGCCUGAGCUCUGUUGAAUUGGAUAAAUGCCCCUAUAAGAUGCCCAAGAGAGGAAGAGACCCAUGUAAGAUGGUGACGUUCUGUGAAUCAGAGAAGUGGGCUCUCACCAGACCCUGAAUGUGCUAGUGCCCUGAUCUUGGACUUCCAGCCUCCAGAACUGUGAGAAAUAAAUUUCUUGGUUUAUAAGCUACCCAGCUUGUGCUAUUUUUGUUAUAGCAGCUUGAACAGGCUAAGACACUGCAUAAUUUAUUUGUAUAUUUCUGAUGCUUUAUGGAUGAAUCAAAAGACAACAGGUGUCUUUGAGUUAGCUACAAGCUGUCAUUUUUGGUUUUCUUUUAGAGAGAGGGUUUCAUUCUGUCACUCAGCUGGAGUACAUUGAUGCCAUCACCGCUUACUUGCAGCCUCUCAAACUCCUCAGCUUAAUCAGCAAUCCUUCCACUUUGUCUUCCCAAGUAGCAGGGACUACAGGUGCGCACCAGCACACCCGGCUGAUUUUUUUUUUUUUUUUUUAACAGACAGGGUUUCACUAUGUUGCCCAGGCUAGUCUCAAACUCCUGGGCUCAAGCAAUCCUCCUGUCUUGGCCUCCCAAAGUGUCAGGAUUACAGGCAUGAGCCACAGAGCCUGGCCUACAGGCUGUCUUUAAAAGGAACAUUGACUAAGCAGAGCAAGCUUCUCUUUGGGAGCCAGAUAAUGAAAAUUAAGAGAUCAUGGCCAGGCUGAGGAUGAGGACACAAUUAUUGGCAAGCUUUUGUUAGUUUCACAUUCAGUCUUGGCUCACAUGCAGGUGUGCCUUCCUUUAAGAAAAUGUGGAGAACAGGUUUUAAAAGUGAGGUGUGUAUUUCACUUUCGAAGUGUUCUUUCGGGUGCCUCAGACUCAGCCUGUCUAAAAGGAAUUCCUGUGUGGGGUUCUGAUUCCACCUCUGAAAUUGCUCAGGUCUCCACUGUCACUACAGGGCCAAGAUCAGCCUCUCUUGCCUGGAUCACAGUAGGGGCCUGAGUGAUUCUUCUGAGUCCAGAUCAAAUCUUGUUACUUUUUUUUUUUUUUUUUUUUUUUUUUGAGACAGAGUUUCGCUCUGUCGCCCAGGCUGGAGUGCAGUGGCGCAAACUCGGCUCACUGCAACCUCUGCCUCCUGGGUUCAUGCCAUUCUCCUGCCUCAGCCUCCUGAGUAGCUGGGACUACAGACGCCCGCCAUCACGCCCGGCUAAUUUUUUUUUUUUUUUUUGGUAUUUUUUAGUAGAGACGGGGUUUCACCGUGUUAGCCAGGAUGGUCUCGAUCUCCUGACCUUGUGAUCCGCCCACCUUGGCCUCCCAAAGUGCUGGGAUUACAGGUGUGAGCCACCGCGCCCGGCCAAAUCUUGUUACUUCUUUAGGUUGAUGUUCAGGCCCCUGAGUCCCACCAUAGAGGCUGCUGUCACCUGGCCUCUACCAGUUCACUAUCCCCACCUUGUGCCUUUUCCUCUGGAUUGUUUGUGUUUGGGGGCUGCCAUCCAGGCCUGCAGGCCUGUGUGUGUGGGGUAUUGAUGCCACGUUUUAAUUUUGGCUGUAUUCAUCGGUGCAUUGUUAGGUUAAGUGCCCUUUUGGGAAGUGAAAUUGAUACUGUUACCCAUUCACAGAUGUUGGGGUUUCUGGGAUGCUCAUAGAACCCUCUUCCUGCCCAAGCUUUGAAAAAGUUAAAAACCGUAAGGAAAGUGAAAGUAGAGGCCCACAUAAUCAUUUAUUAUUGAUAGAGGCAAGGUUGGAGGCCACAGCUUGUUGUGAAAACCAAAUGGUCCUGCCAGCAGAGUCUCAGGAUUAGGCCAUUUAACUUACUGGGCCCAGGUGGCAUGUUGCCUGCACGGUGGCCUGGUCCUUGAGCAGGAGGAGGCCGGGAAUGAACCAUUUUCUAAUCAGAUAAGUCCCUGCACUUCUCAGGAGUGGAAGAGUCCCAGAGUUAACUCAUCGAUCCCCUCACAGGCGAAGCGGGGAAGAAGCACUUCUCACUAACAGGCUUCUCAAAAACUCUUCUUCCCUGUAGUGAUUGUUUCAAUAUUAAUAAGAAGAAGCUGUUCUUUCUACAAAUAGGUUAACUACUGGAAAUUUAAUAGAGUAUUUAUUUAAUUCAAGGAGCUAAACAUCUUACCCUUCCUUCAUAUGAACAUUGAUAUUUAGAAUAUAUUUAUUGACAAAAUGAUAAAACAAGAAAUAUUUAACAGUUUAUUUUUCUGUAAGCAAUUCUAAAUGUCUUAUAAUAGCAUGAAUAAAUUCAGCAACCAAAGAAUUAUGUUAGGGUCCUUCCUUGUUGGUGAUUUGGGGCCCAGUUCUGCUUUGAUGGAGCUCUCCUGUGAAGUUAGUUUCAGCAGACGAUGCCUCAGUGGCAGUGUGUGUUUGAAAUUCGUUUCACAUGUGGGAAACACAUAGGGCAGUUUUCUUAUAGCAUGUGAGUGUUGGGGAGGCUUUUCUAGUGUGAUGUUCUGUAUGUUUUGUGUUGUUUCAUGAGGGAAAAUGGAUUUGAGAGAGUGAGCGGUGAGCUAAGAGCAUGCAGUAUAUUCAGGGUAAGCCUGAAUUGGGCAUCAGCAGAACCACUUCAAGACUAGCCCUUUGACUUUCCGGAAUCCUGGUUAGUUUUAAGCUAGAACCUUCUUUUCUUUCUCCUCUUCUUUGUGUCUAGCCUCCACCCUCACCCCCAUCUUCAGCUUAAAACCUCUUACAAAUAGCAUCCCAAAGGCAUCAUUCAUGAGGCUGAACAGUUUUGAAAAGAGCAAGGGAAGUUACUCACUUUUUUCCCAGUGAGCUCUAUGGGCAGUGGAACUCUAAGGUAAUUGUCAACCAUUGUGGAAAGCAAUAUUUUCAUUUGGUUAACAUAUUUGGACCCAUUCGAUCCUCGGUACUAGCAUUAGAAAGAUGAUUUCCAUCUAUUCCUAAUGAAAAUAGGUUUUAUUUCUUUGAAACAUUUAAAGGAACAAAAGCUUAAAUUCCAAAUAUUCCUAAAACCCUAAAAAGGGUUUCAUUUUCGAAUGAGCAUUGGAAGAAAAUGGUCAUUUGUAGCACAGACUCUACCUAAACAUAGUCCACCAUUCCCUCCCUAUUGAAAGUUAGACAGUUCAUAUGAAAGUCAGGAAUCUGAAAUCCUCUUUGGUUGGGGGAGCACAAAAGAUGACUUUUGCAGACCCAGAGCAGAGUUUGAGUCGGGUGGAAUGAGAUUAGUGUGCUGGGGGGAACGUCCGGACCCCUGGCCUUCUCUCCUUUGUGAGGAAUGUGACAGCUGAAAGGAGUCAGAAGCCGCCCGGUGCAGCAGUGACAGCCCAGCAGUGACAGCCCAGCACAAAGGGUGGUGUGCUUUCCGACCUCUGGCCGCCCUUUGCUAGACCUUCAAUUGUAGUUUGGGGCCCAGACUUUGCAUUUUUCUCUUUUAUGGCUUAAUUUAAUUUUAUUUCAACCAGUUUAUUAGAGUGAAGGCCUUCUUUGUUGCCCCGAGGCUUUGUGCCCAUUGGACUGGAAAUUAGAUGAGCUGGGGGUAAGUAUUCUUUGUAUGCAUGAGAGAGUUGGUGACUGGGAAGACACUGAGGGCCAGACCUCACUAGCCAGUGGACCAAUGAUUUCAACCUAGCAACAUCACUUAUUACUAAGGGAAGGGGCAGUUGAAAAGUGGUAAGCAAGGUAAGUCAUCACUAGCAGCUAGCCACGGUUGUGUAGCUGUUCCUGUUCCUCCGAAUGGGCACCUUGGCUGUGUUUCUUUUGUGCCCUCUCAAACUUGGCUCCAUAUUGGAAUCACUGGGAGCAUUGACAACAACAACAAAAACAGAUGCCUGGGCCCCUGCAGAGCUUCUGGUUUAAUUGGAAUGGGUGCAGCCUGGGUGUGGGCGCUGCAGAUCUUCAGGUGAUGGUACAGUGUAGCCGCAGUGGAACACCACUGGCCUGCCUGAGACCUGAGGUGCUUGGGCAUUACCUGCAGGCUUUAUAAAAAAGUUAAAUGGUGUUAGAAUAUUUCAGGGGAGGUUCUGAUUAGAUCUAAGAAUAAGCAUAUGAAAUUUAGAGACUAGGACUUUUUAGGGUUGUUGAACUGGAAAAACUUUGGUGGGAACAAGGGAGCUUAUUGAUUUUUAAAAAAAAAACUUAAAAAGAAUAGCUAGAAAGAGGCUGGGUAAAGGGGCAUUGAAAUUGACUCCCUUAAGCACUGGUCCCAAGAUAUUUGUUUUUCCCAGAAGGAGAGUGAGGAUGGAAACUAAAGAAAUAAAAACUGUCUGGCCAUAGCUACUCCAGACAGAGCGAUGGCUGUGGGUGAUGAUGAGCAUAAAAUGAGGUGAGGGCAGGAGUCCCCGCCCUGGCUCCGCUCGGUGUUCACUCACGUCUCUCCUGUGUGCUCAUCUUUGACACCAGCUCCUCUGACUCAACUUUUCCCCUUGUUUUUACUCUCUCCUUAGCACCAGCUGUUGAUUUUUAUUCCUUGCUUUUUCCCCACAGCCAGCUCUGCCCGUAGCAGCUCUACCACUGUCUCCUUUCCCCUCUGGUGGCAACGCUCUCCUUUGUUCAUGUUUUACCUUCACUUCUUAUGUUAUCAGUUCCAUGGAAUCAGUAGGAGUCACACUCUACAAGCCUGUUCUAGUCCGACUGGGCAGAUAGAGUGAGGUCAUCUCACUCUAUCUGGAGAGGAGACUGGAGGGGAGUGCUGAGGAUGCUGCCAGGGUGGGGUUUUGAGAUUUAAUAGGGGGCUAAGGUCAGGCUUGUCGGAGACAGGUUAGAGAUUACUAGAGGGUCAGAGGUCCCACCGCUUGGGCAGGAGGGCAGGAGCCAGCUGAGCAGGGCUGACUGAGGGGCCUGAGCUUGCCCUUGUGGCUUUGAGGCUGGGCCAUUUAGACUGUGCCUGCCCAAGCAGGGUCUGCCCUGGAUGUCCACGGAGUAUAAAGAGGCCCCUUAGGUGAGGGCGGUACAACCAUUUGCUGAAAGGUGACUUUUCUAAAGACCUGUUCCUACUUUGAAUAUUGCUUAUUUGACACGAUUUAAGUGGGAUGUUUUAAUUUUUAUUUAUUUAUUUUUGUGUGUGCGUGUGUGUUACUGAGAAUUUGUAUCUUUUCAUUUAAUUUCAACAACUUGUUGGAAAAUGCUGGCCACUCUGACUUCUAAGAUACUUAGUGACAUUUUAUAGAUAGUUUGGAUUGUUUCUAUGUAAUCAUUUGAACAAAACCAUAACAAAUCGUUUUAUGAAAAGCACCCUGGAGAUGGUAAAUUCUGAAACCAAACUAAAAUUGGUUUCAGAAUUCUUAUUCUGCGAGCUACAUUUAAAAAAAUGUAAUGUCUCCAGAUUAGGCCUUAAAAUGAAGCGCCCCCAUUAAUAUCCUGCUUAUGUUCAGGAACAUCUAGAAAAAGGUGUCAGUGCAGAAGCUGAAAGCACACAGCCCGUGCGUGCUGAGCGGGUUCCUCACCCCAGCCUUUCUCCCAGGCUGCAGAAAGGACUCAGGAAAUGUGGCCCAUCAUUAUUACUUAUGCUUGUUAAACAGGAAUUGACCAGAUACCUCAUUUUAACAUUUUAAAGAUAUCUCUAUGAGAGAGUUGAAUAUUUGACUUAGGACUUUUAGAAAAAUAUAUAUUAUUGUUUUUCUUAAAUGUGAUGUUUUGUGUUUGUUGUAAAUACGUGAUACAAUAUGUAAUAAUUUAUGCAGCCCUUGAACACGCUGUCUUCAGAGUCGUUUUGCAGCUGCUGUCUGAGUUUCCUAAGUCAUUUGGAUUUACUUGGGUGUGUUCAGCCCAGAUAAAAAUGUGGAUCUACCUGAAUGUGUCCAGCACCUGCACCACUAUUAAAACCGAGAAUUUCCUGAGGUCAGGAAUUACAGGGAACUGAUUCUCUUCAUUACUUGGGACUAAUUUCCCCUUCUUCCAUUUUUCCAGUCGUACAGCAGAAGACUAUGAAAUAGAGGAUUUAAGGAGAGAAGAAAAGGGCAUUUUCACCUUUUUUUUUUUUUCCUGUGAACAUUCGGAGAGGAUAAACUGAAGCUUGAAAUAUUAGUGCUCAUUUUAAUUUUAUAUUAAAUUAGUUUUAUUACAAGUUUUCUAAGGUUCUUUAUGGAAAGGUUAAAAAAGAUUUGUUGUUGUUGUUGUUUAGUUCUAGAAAACCUGGCAGUUUACAAAGUUUUGGGGUAACAGUAAACUUUCCUUCCUUUGAUUCACUAAGUUUUUCUUAGUCUUUCAAUACCUGAGGGCCAGGAGUGUAUAGACUACAUGAUAAAUCAGUUUUUUAUUUUAUUUUCACAUAUAAACCAGAGUUAAUUUGAUUUAAGAUCAACAGACUUGAUUUAUAAAAGAAUACUUGUAUUUUUAGAUCUGAACAUUUUAGGUGGCUACAAUUUUACCCCAAAUUAAGAACCUUUGCAAACCAAGUGGCAGGUGGUCUCAUUCAGCUAUACCAGUUGAGAUGUGUUUACCUCUGGAGAUGGAGUGAAAGAAAUUGUAUCUGGCAGAUAGCGGAGGAAAAUUGUCUUCAUGGCUAAUUAUUCAGUGACUUCUAUCUAUGCAGCUUCCCAUUUUAAUUCUGACGGUAAGUGUCUGCAAAUGUCUGUGCUAAAUAUUCCUCUUGCUUUCAGACAGCCUCUAAGUAAGUGUGUGUGUGUAAGAAUUGAUAACUUUAUAUUUUUUUCCUCUCUUUUCUCUGGUAGUUUAUUUUUAGUAGUAAAAUAGUGGCAAUGGAUAAUUCAGUCACGUUUUCCUUCUUUUUCUUAUUCUGGUAGCCCCUUCCUAAGAGUGAUUAGUGGGAAAAAAAGGGACAUAAGGGCUCAGUCCCACUAGAAGCACCCAUAGAAGUGGCCCUUUAUGAUGGCAGGCGGCACUUACAGGCUUAGGCUGUUGCCAUUUCAACUGUGUUCUUAUUUUUUUAAGCAAGAGUCUCAGCCAGUUCUAGUAAAUUAAAAAUUAGAACAUAAGAAGUGAGGAACAAGAGUUCCUCUUGGGCUGGGAUAAACUGGAUUUUGAAGUAGAGCAACCUCCGUUCACUGACUCCUUGGUCAGGAGUUUAUUGGUACAAGGGCUCGGAAGCAUUUUCCUCUCUCCUUGUCAUAAGGUACCGCAUCUUUUUGAUUUUCUUAGACUCUGCCCUAACAUGGCCUCACUAAGGAGACUAGAAAACUGAGAGAAAACCUUGCCAGUCAGUAAACUGCAUCACAAGGCCUGAAGAGAGAGCUUAAAGGCAACACACAACAAAAGGCAGAGGUGCCAGAUGGCUAUGCCAUUCUGGGUUAAAGGUUAAACCUCAUCCUCCCUGGAGACCAGCCAGAGGCAGCCACAUUCCUGGCCCUGGUGGGGGCUCCUGGCCCAAGGGCUCCACUGCCCAUCCUCGGCAGACCCAGGGAGGAGCUGGGUUUGGUGUAGAACAGGUAAUGGGCAGCACAGUACUCAUGAGUAGCAAACCUUACAGGACUGAUCCCGUCAUGACCAAUAUGGAAAUGUCAGUACUCGAGUACCUGUGUGUGUUGAUCUUCUCUCUGAAAUAUAAACAGCUAAAUUAUUUUCCAAUUUGGUCAAGGAAAUAGGGAAUCACAUGUGAACUAUUUUUGUAAUAGGCCGAGUUACUAAUUUUUGUUUAACUAACUCUUUCCAUUUAAAUGCUUUUUGGCUGUUUUGUCAUUGUUCCUAUGUGGGCUGCUAUUUUCAGAUAGGGUGCUGGAGGUCAGUAAGGCCAAGAGAGACGGUGAGCACUCAUCACUGCUCCCCUGUGUUGGCUGCACUCCGGAAAAUGGGCACACACCUUGAAAUCAGCCGUGUUCUGAUUUACCCGGCUUUCCGUUAACCAGCCCUUUAACUUGACCAAGGUUUAUUCCCUUUUGUUUGCUGUAAACUAUGUUGAGGAAACUCUUACAAAGCACAGUCCUUCCUGUUUGUAUUGUCUGCAUUUUAGGUUGAUGGGGUGGGUUUCAUUUCUCUCUUAGAGUCACUUCUCUAAUCCAGUUUCUUUUGUCUAAUGCAUGGUAAAGAAUUCACUGUUCGAUAUGACUGACUUUGGUCUGCAGUUAGUUGGAAGAUCUCAUAUUCUUUCACUGCAGGACAAUUUUUUUUUUCCUUUUUUUGUUUUUUUAUGGUGGUAGAGAUAUUGGGAGGAAUGCAGGGAUGGAACUAAUUUGUGUGUGGCUGGUUGCAUGGGCGAGGCCCAAUGCCAUGUGCUUCUCUAAGCCAUGUUCCCGUUCAGGAAGUAGGUAGGGCCCGAGAGCUAGGGUCUGAAUCAGCAUGUGACAUCAGGUCCACUGUGUUUCUCCUCCAUACCCUCUGCUUUCCAGAAAACAGUGUGUAUGAACUCCAGCUCACUUUCUUCCAGCAGUCUUGUUAAAAUGCUGGUGCUAUCACUGAGUUAAAUUUCUUAUUUCUCCUUCAACUUUAUUAAGUUUGGUUUAAUUUAUUUACUUUCUUCAGACUCAAGUUGUAUACAAAAAUAAAUGGAGCUUUAUUGAAUCUCACUGCGCAAUUGGUGACACACACCUUUUAGAGAAAUAAAGUCAAGAGUCAUUUUUAUGGGGCAUCUUGAGAUAAACUCUUGAGGGGUUUUGUGUAGCCUGCGUGGGAGGGCCCUGGAGGUGGAGGUGAGAGACUGUGGGAAUUGGGGAGGUGAGGACUGUCUGUUCCAUGAUGUGCUCCAGCAAGGUGUCUGGGGACUUGACUUCCCUUGUGGGGAAGAGGAUAGGAGAGAUGGAAUUCCCGGAUUGCGUUGCUGGAUUGCAGGCACACUCCAGUGGGCUCUGGAAGCCCUCAGAGGAACCCUUGACUUGAGAUAGAGCGAUGACUUCCUGUUCUGUGAUUCGUCCUCCUUGGCUGGAUGGUUUCUGAACUGCUGCAGGAAGUGUCUGUUUAGUUGUGCAAGUAUUGUUUCAGGAAUUAGAAGUUGUGUUUCCUUUCCUGAAACGCAUAUGCCUUACUAUAGAUAAGGAGAUUCUUUUUUCUUUUUUAUAGUUCUUAUACCUCAAGCAUGCCAUUUUUCUAAACAGGAGCCUAUAUGUGAAUGCACUUAUCAGUUUUCCCCUGGGUUCAGUAAAAUGGAUUUGUCUUAGAUUCCUGUAGUAAAGUUGUUGACAGAGAGUUGAGGGAAGAUCAGCUGAAAAGCAUCCAAGUGUGGAAUCCACUGGAGAACAGUGCUUUGCCCAUUUAAGUGUCUGACAACUGAGUUAUUUGUAAGUUAUGCCAAGGAUAUUUUUAGAACUCAGUAUCUUAUCCUUAGGUUACCAAUUAUUUUGAUUCCCCAACAGACUCCAAAGGGUACAAGAGAAGUGAGAUUGGAAAAAAGAAUUUCUGCGAAGAGAAGCUCAACUGAAUCUUAACUAUGGUAAUUAAUUGGCAGAAAAUCAAUAAUUCAGUGAGAAGCCUCUCAGCCAAUGGUGGCAAAAGACAAUGUAGUGAAUGUUAGUGGAUUUGGGAGAGUAUACAAGUACCAGUGAGCUAACUGGGUGAAUUUACAUACUGUGUUACCGUAGUGUUACACAAGACUAGUCAUUUGGGAAAUUGAUGGAAGAUUAAUGGAGAUCCAAAUGUUUAAAUAGUUUAAUCAUUGUCUGACCCUAAAGAGAAACCUCAGUGAAUACGUAUUUGGCUUAAUGAAUUGAAAUGAAACUGCGUUUUGUCACCCGAUGGUGAGGAAAUUUUAGCUCACCUGCUUUAUGUCUCAAAUUCUUUUCCAUAAACGUGCCCCUGUGUUUCCUUGAGGGAACUGCCACCUAAAUGUUUCUUUCAGAUAGUGCUUCUCAAUUAUUUUAGUCUCAUGCCUUUUUUUUACACUCUGGAAAAUAAUUGAGGACUCCAAAGAGUUUUUGUUUAUGUGAGUUCUAUCAAUCACAUAAUCUACCAUAUCAGAAAUAAAAAAGGGAUUUUAGAAAUCAUUAUUGAAUUUAAAAUAACAAUAUAACCACCUGUAUGUUAACAUAAAUAAUACUUUCGUGAAAAAUAACUAUUUUCCAAAACUAAGACACUUAUUGAGAAGUAUGCUUCGUUAUUUUUUGCGAAUAUCUUUAAUAUCUGGCUUAUUAGAAGACAGCUGUUUUCUUGCCUUGCAUCUGCAUUCAAUCUGUUGUGAUAUGUAGCUGUGGUUGCCAUCCAACCAAAGAAAACCUAGCCUCACACAGGUUUGUAGUUGGAAAAGGGAGUGCUUGAAUUUCCUUUCAGAUAAUAGUGGAUCUUCUUUGAUAUAACACUAGAGAAGUGGUAUCUCAAAGUUUGGUCGAGAUGUAUGUAGAUCCUGAAACCCUAUCUAUGAACUUUAAAAACUCUGUUUUAGGUAUUAUUUUGAAUAUCAUGCAUUGGCCACUUAGAAAAAUCUCCCAAAUGUUUAUAUAUUUCACUUGUAAUAUCAAAAAUUCUUGUCAUGAAUCAGAAAAUUCUUAAGUGUAGGGAAAUUGUCAAGAUCACAGUGGUUAUUCAAGUUUUAAGAAAGUCUAAAAUUUUCAUAAAAGCUUAAUCUUACUGUUUUCCUCGAAAAUGGGCCUGUUUUGUUUCUUUUCUUUAAAAUGCCUGCCAGAUAGCCUUGUCGGAAUAACCAUUGUUUAUAUAUCGCUCUGUCAAGUACAAGGUUGGGUUCAAUGAAGAAAAGUGGCUCAUCACCUCAUAGGUCCACCCCACAGGUGCUGACCCUUGCGACAGCCACCAGUAUAUGCUGCAACAGGGCUUUCCCUUCCUUCACACAGAGUCAUAGUGUGUGUGUGCUCAAGAGUCAAGGCGUAAUAAAAUCAGUUUUUUACUUCUCCAUUGUAUUAGUCCGUUUUCCUGCUGCUGAUAAAGACAUACCCGAGACUGGGCAGUUUACAAAAGAAAGAGGUUUAAUGGACCCACAGUACCACAUGGCUGGGGAGGCCUCACAAUCAUGGUGGAAGGUGAAAGGCACGUCUCACAUGGCGGCAGAUAAGAGAAGAGUGAGAGCCAAGUGGAAGGGAUUUCCCCUUCUAAAACCAUCAGAUCUUGUGAGACUUAUUCACUGCCACAAGAACAGUAUGGGGGAAACCGCCACCAUGGUUUAGUUAUCUCGCACUGGGUCCCUCCCACAACACGAGGGAAUUAUGGGAGCUACAGUUCGAGAUGAGAUUUGGGUGGGGACACAGCCAAAUCAUAUCAUCCAUCAAGGACAAUAAGUGAGGUGACUGAUCUCUUCAUUUAUUUUAACUGCAGUUAUGUGGUAAGAUGACAGCUAGUAAGUACAGUGUGGGGCCACUGCCUUGCUGUGUAGUAAGGUACACACAUUUUUACAUGCUGUUGCUCUUGUACUGUUGAUGCUGUACAAAAAGGCAAAUAACAGCUUUAGAAUUCUAGUUUGACCUCACAGAUCCAGUUGAAGAGCCUUGGGGAUCCUAAGGGGCCCGUGGUUCAUACUUUUUGAGAACCACGACUUUAAGACAUACAGGAAAGGUGCUAAAUGAGACAGAACUAGACUUGACUCGUUAUGAACUUAGUAUUACAGAAAUGGGUCAGAUACCUCAUACGUGUGGUGAUAGACGUGUGGGGCCAUGUGGGAGGGAUGUGUAAGAGAGUUCCUGGAGUGUGGCACUUUGACUGGGGCUGUUGACUCCUGUGUCCUGAACAUCUAAAUCUGUACCUGGUGUAUCAGUUCAUACUUUAUGUAGCAGUUUGAAUAAUUAGGGCAAGUGUAAUGGCUGCAUAAAUUCAUUAGUUUUUAAAAAGUCAAAUGGGUUUUGUGUUCAUAAUAAAGAUUAGUCAAGGUAAUCUUUUUGUAGUAUAAAAGUAAUAAAGUUGUGAAAUAUAGCUGCACAGCCCCUCCCAUCCCACCUUCCUGUGAUACCGUCAUCCUCAGUCUCCCUACCCUUGUAUGUCUGUUUCCUAUUACCAUCAAGGCCCAUGACACCAGCUGUGUAGACAUACUCCAAAAAUAAUAGACGCAGUCUUUAUCAUUAUUCACUUAAAAAGCCAACCAGUGUUCUUUCCCCUGAUUGGGAAUGUGCCCAGUAUGAAGGGACAGCAUCACAUUGGUUAUGUAAUUGAUGCUGUUUGUGACAAAGACUCCUGUUUCACUCCUGUUUUCCCAGCAGUUUCGCAUUGUAACUAGGUAGUGAUGAUGUUUGCUUGUUUUCUGUGUAUGAAGAAUCACAAGUGUGUUUUUCUUGGGUGGCUCUAGAAGAGAAAGCUUUCAUGCCUAGAAGAAUAUCUUGUUAUUUCUAUAGAAGCUUUUUAAAAAUUCUUCAUUAAAAGAAAUUUUAAGUCAUUUAGAGUAGCUGUUUUUGUGUGAGUUGAUAUUUUGACCCAUUUUAUUUUUCUCUUCAGUUUUCUGAUUUGUGUGAUUACGUGACGAGCUCUUCCUGUGAAUCUCGAACACUCAGGUUGGAGUCGUUCGGUCUUUGGAGCCUUUUGGGAGGAAGCCAGGUGCUCUUCAAUUGCCCUUUGCAGUAGGACUCCCUGGUAAUAACUGUGGCGAUGAUGAACUUGUCUAGAUAAAAUGACAUCUGAUAAAAUAUUAAUAAAUACAUUGUAGUGGACACCUGCUUCUGAGGAUGUGGAUGUGUGAAACCUAGACAUUCAAUUUAUGAAUGUCUUUUUAAUUGACUCCUCUGGACACAGAGAGAGGACCCACAUGAUCACUGAGAAAAUAUCAGAGUACAGGUGGCAGAACUGUGGCAGAAUCCCCUGUGCAAACUGUAUCGCUGUGCGGAGACAGAGCUAACAAACAGGGUCUCAAGGAGAAACCGAGUCUUGUGCUUUGCUUUCAUGAGGGAUUUUUCUGAGUUAGCUGAUGAAGCCAAGCUAAGUAAAUAUUAUCUUCUUUUUGUGUUGGCCUUUUGUUUUGAAAUAUUCCAACUCUAUUUCCUUCAUAGUUUUCUCUUUAUUGCUGUUAUUAUUUUUACAGAUUAGAGGUACCACCUUUUCCAGUCUUGCUCAUCAUGGUUUUUCCUACUUCAAGCUGUGAACUAUUUAAUUCAGUUCAGCAAGCAUUUUUGGAGUGUUUGCAAGUCAGUAGCUGUGUUAUUACCAAACCUGCCAUCUUGACUUUCUGCUGUUGCUAUAAGCCCUUUGAUUUGCAUGUUCAGUAUCAGCACUCUUAGCAGCUUCUUCUCUGUGUUUGCCUCCCUUGGUAGGUUUUUAGAUUAAGGGAACCUUGUUAUGGAGAAUGAGGCUUCCAGGAUUGGCCUUCUUCCUCCUUUGUUCUCUUUGUAUGGUUUCAUUGUUCUACUUUACCCUUUUACAUGUGCACAGAGCUUCCAGUAUCAAGCUGUUCCUUGGAGUAGGAAGUAGUUUUGGAGAUGAGAAACACAGAGAGAGGAGGAGAGAGAAUAUUAGAGAAGAAAAUUAUUCUCUUUGGAUCAGUUUCCAUUAGGCAUUAACCAUUGGCCUGUCCCUUUCCCCACUGCCCCUUAGACACUGUAGGUCUUCAUCUGUGCUUAUAUAAUGAGGUCUGAAUUGUUCUGUGGUGAUCCUAUGACCAUUUCCAUAUAUGAGAUUGUAAAUAUCUUCUUUUACUGUGGGGAGAAAGGCACUUAGCUAGAAAAUAAGAGUAAGCCUCCAGAAGAGUAUAUUCUGCUAUGUUUAUAGAACUGUCAUCUUUGGUUCUAAUACAUUGCUGCUGAGAAAAUUGAUAGAAGUUGUGUUUACUUGAAUACAGCAAAUUACCCAAAUGGAUAGGUAAAGAUUAUUCACUUUUAUUACAUUUCAAAUGGUUUCAUUGUAUUUCCCCAAAUUGUACAUUUAUUACAGAAGUUAGCUUUGUGUUUCUACUUUUAGGUGUAUAAAAAUCAAGAUCUCUACCCCAAUUGAGGAGAUAUAUAAUGGUUUAAAUCUGAACACUGUGAAGUAAUGGGGGCUUAAAUGAAAUAUCCCCUUACUACUUAGUGAAUGUUUGAUGUAAAUCAGCCACAAUACUUCCUCUCUCCCCCAUAUAUGGAUGGCAACAUAGUUAUAUAACCUUCUAAUGAUGGAUUUAUUUAUUCUCUUCCAGAAGUGCUCAAGCCUAUUGCAGACAAAUUUCUACAAAUUUAUUUUUCCUUUUUAAUUUUUCUUCUGUCUGGUUGACCUAACUCUUCACAGGUUUCCAUCUAGCGUUUUGUAUAAGUAGUCAUUUAAGUAUGAUUUAAGAAGUUCAUCUGAGAAUGGAUACUUUCCCUUUGUAGGGGCCAAGGGAAAACUUCCCUGUCACCCUCUGAAAGGUUCACUGAAAAUCAUUGACAAGAGGUAGAUUAAUGAGAGGAAAGGCAUACAAAUUUGUUUGAUCACAUUUUUAUAUCACAUGAGAGCCUUCAGAAUGAAGACCCAAAGAUACAGGAUAAACUGUCCAUUUUUAUGCUUAGGUUCAACAAAGUAUGGUCAGCUGUGCAGAAAUAUGAUUGGACUAGGCCAAGAUGGGCAGAUCACACGGUCUCUAUCGAGACCAUCCUGGCCAACAUGCUGAAAGCCCGUCUCUACUAAAAAUGCAAAAAUUCGCUGGGCGUGGUGGCAUGCACCUGUAGUCUCAUCUACUCGGGAGGCUGAGGCAGGAGAAUCGCUUGAACCUGGGAGGCGGAGGUUGCAGUGAGCAGAGAUCGCACCACUAUACUCCAGCCUGCUGAUAGAGUGAGACUCCGUCUAAAAAAAAAAAGAUUGGACUAAAAGGAUAUGAUUGAUUUCUAACCGACUGAAUGGGGAAGCCCAGCAAGGCCUGUCUGUCUAGAAUUCUUCUUGGCCUCUCUGAGUAUGUUCUCCUUCCUUCUGGGUAUGGUGCAGGACUCUCUUUGGAAUGGGCAUCUUAUGAUCUACAAUCAAACAUGGUAGUUCAGAUAAUUUCUUUAUGGCCAGUUUUUAUACAGAGAGCGGGGAAGAGUUAAUACGUUUAGGUUUUAUAGCUAGCUUUGGGCAAAAGGGAUUCUAGUUUCUAUGACCUGUCUUUGGGAAGAGGGAUUCUAGUUUCUAUGGCUUGCUUCGAAGGAGAAUGAGAGACCAGAGACAGGAGGGCAGAGAGAGCUCCUUCUGAGGCCUUUGUUACAUCAUUUUCUGAGCCCCAGCAUCUUUCAGUGUCAGAAACAGAGAUAGUACUAUUAGCAGAGUUAUCAGUUUGAGACAUAAUUACCUUUCAUGGACACCUGUAGUUGUUUGAGUGAAUUUAGACUUCCUUAGUUUAUUACAGUUGCUUUUAGUAGCUGUCCUUAAAAUAGAGAAUAUUCUUGAAUUUAACACAUACAGUUUAUUCUCUCCUCUCUUUAUUGAUUUAAUGAGUACUAUUUCAGGUUUAUAAUAGAAUUCCCCAGUCUUGAAAUGUUUAUGGCAUUGAAACAUCAUUAAGUUAGAGCUUUAUUCAGCCUACACAGAGAAUGGAGGACACUAUGGUUUUCACUGUGCUCCAUUUGACCAUGGAUGGUCUUCAGGCUGUAUCACUAUUCAACUCUUAAGAUAACUAAUAUAAGCUACAACUUUAAUGAGUGAUAUUUUCUCAUUUUUAGUGUUUUGCUUGUCUACAAGCAGAUGGUAAAAGCAAACUAGUAAAUGAUGGAAAAACCUGUAUCAGCUAUAUAUGCUAAAUUUUAUGUCCUGUUUUUUUCCUGGAUAGUCGUGCUUGUGAUGAUGCCUAUUACUUCCUAACUUAUAUCUUUUCUGCUAAUAAAAUUGUCCCUGCUUCCCAUACUAAAAUGAUAUCAUUAUUUGUAAUGUUUUACAAAUUGGGUGGAAGAGGUGUGUGUUCACCAAGCAGCAUCAUGACUUUUCACUGCUCCACCCUUUACCCAGGCAAGUUGGAAGAACAACUAUUUGAGUGUGAGAACAAGAGCACCAGGACAAGAAGCUGGAAAAAUAAAUAGGAGAUAUUGCUAGUGGCCUGGUUGCCUUGACUAGAAAUUUGCGCUUUGUGUUCAUUGUGGAGUAGUUAAAGCUUUUUAGCUUGAAUUUAGCAGGGAUGUAUUGGUUUCCAACGAGUCUUCCUUAUAUAUCUUGUUUGUGGGAAUUACUGAAAGAGCCACAGAAUUUUCAACACCACAUGGAGGCUAUCCCAAUAAUCACAAUAACUUAAUUAUUUAUUCUUAAAAGCUCAGAGAAGAAUUAAUGUAAAAAAUUAUGGGAACCCUUAUACACUGUUGGGGGGAAUGCAGAUUAGUUCACCCAGUGUGGAAAGCAGUUUGGAGAUUUCUCAAAGACCUUAGAACUACCAUUCGACCCAGCAAUUCCAUUACUGGGUAUAUAACCAAAGGAAAAUAGAUCAUAUACCAAAAAGACACAUGCACUCUUAUGUGUAUCACUGUGCUGUUCACAACAGCAAAGACAUGGGAUCAACCUAGGUGCCCAUCAGUGGUGGAUUAAAUAAAGAAAAUGUGGUAUAUAUACACUAUGGAAUACUGUGUAGUCAUGAAAAGAAUGAAAUCACGUCGUUCAUACCAACAUGGAUGGAGUUGGAAACCAUAAUCCUAAGCAAACCAAUGCAGGUAUAGAAAACUAAAUAUUACAUGUUCUCAUUAAUAAGUGGGAUCUAAAUAUUGAGCACCUAUGGAUGUAAACAUGGGAAUAAGAUACUGCAGACUAGUAGAGGGAGGAAGGGAGGGAGGGAAGGAAGGAGAGGAUGGGGUAAAACACUAUCUCUUGGGUACUGUGCUCACUGCCGGGGUGCAAUAUACCCAUGUAACAAACCUGCACAUGUACCCCCUGUAUCUAAAAUAAAAGUUGAAAAAAAAAUUAUGGAAAAAGCAUAGACAGUGAAUGAAAUUAAUCAUGACAUCAUCAUCAACAAAUGUUUCUUGAAUGCAACAAGCUUGCCUGCUUAUUCAUUUCACCAACCAUUUAUUAUUAUGCAUAAGGCUUCUGCCCAUUAAGAAUUCACAGUUGAAGGUUGCAGACAUAUCUAUCAAGAAGUUACAUAAGAGACUGAAAAAUGUUCCAGCAAAAGGUACAAGUAGUAUUCUAAGUGAGUAGUAGAGAGGAAGAGACACUUUUCUAUCUAGGAAGUUUUUCUUUAACAGUUUUUCUCUUGGAAAUGUCUGAGAAAGUUUUGUGGGGAAUAUGGGGCUUUUAGGCGCAAAGGAUGCUGUUUAUUUUGGGUAAGGGGACGUCUUGAUAGAAGGGACAGAGGCAGGAACCUUUAGGGCAUAUUCAUCUGGGAAAGGUCAUUUAAUGUGUAUUCUGACUGUCAGGUAGGGAAGUUGAGUUACGAAGGUACUUGGGCCAUAUUAAGGAAUUAUUUGAAGGUUAUUUUGAGAUUUAAGUUACACAUAGUAUAGUUUUGAACAGAUGUGUCUGUGUGAGCUGUUGGUUAUCAGUCAAAGAAACUCAAAGUAACUUAAGCAAAAAAAGAAAGGCAUAGCUCAAGUAACUGGGAUGUUUAGGGGUGGCAUACUACAGGCAUUGUUGGAUUCAGGGGCUCAAACAUUGUCAGAAGGCCUCUUUUUUCCUCUCUCUCUCUGUCCUUGCUCUGCCUUCCCUACGUUGAGCUCUGCAUAACAGCCCUUUCUCUGUGAUCUAUGAGACAGUGGCCAGCGGCUGCAGCCCACACCCUCCUAGCUUAGUUCCUUUGGCAGAACUGAACUUCUUAAGAUCCCGACAUCAUCCCAGAGAAAACCGUAUAUGACCUUGCCAUGGCCUGCACAUAUCCUUGAACUAGUCACCGAGCUAAGGGAAUGGUGUGCCCAGAGCAGCUCAGGGGACAGCAUGACAUCAAGGGCAGGGAUGGUUCCUUACAAGAACCAGAACGGAAUGUGGGAAAGGGACACGAGGAGGACAGAAACUUUAGGUGCCAUGGUUGCAGCACAAGAGGGAGGGUAAGAGAAGACUGGAGCUGUUAGCCCAGGUCAGGAACAUGGGUGGAGGAGGAGAUUUGUCAGGAAGGAUGCAGACUCCAUCUUCUGCAUGUUGAGUUAUAGGUGCUAUGGGCCAUUCAUGUGGCAGUUGGCUGUGAGGGCACAAAGGAGAGGGAUAAAGUUAGUGUUGUAGCAGAAUAAAGGAUUGAUGGUAAAGAGAGUGAAGGGAACCAAAGUAUUUUAUCCUGAAAUAUACUUUGACAUAUUUCAAGAUGGCUAUUCACUGGGCUUGAAAUGCAAGAACAGCUGAAAAGCUGUCUUUUGUAGGGGAGAUUUGCAUCUGUAGGGAAUCUGCAUUAAUACAGCCAGGCUUUCUCUAAGGCCCUCCUUUGUCCUCAUCUAGGCAAGAUUAACUGAGAGUCUGACACCUAUAAAGGUCUGAAAAAAAAUUUACCAUCCAUUCUGUCUGAGGGCUGCUACCCAUGUGAGGUUUCAUCUGCAUCAUGAGGCAACCUUUGCUAGCCAGGACUCCUCCCCUUCCCAUAACCUGUCCUGUCAUCAUAACUUGAGGUACCAUCAUAACCUGUUUUUGGCCAUGCUCCUGUCAGGCAUUUUAACCAGAGUGAUUCCAUCUUGAACAGGGGCUGAGUAAAAUGAGGCUGACACCUACUGGGCUGCUUUCCCAGGAGGUUAGACAUUCUUAGUCACAGGAUGAGACAGGAGGUCAGCGCAAGAUAUAGGUCACAAAGACCGUGCUGAUAAAACAGGUUGAGGUAAAGAAGCUGCCAAAACUCACCAAAACCAAGAUGGUGACAAAAGUGACCUCUGGUCAUCCUCAUUGCUCAUUAUAUGCUAAUUAUAAUGCAUCAGCAUGCUAAAAGACACUCCCACCAGUGCCAUGACAGUUUACAAAUGCCAUGGCAACACCAGGAAGUUACUAUUUAGUCUAAAAAGGGGAGGAACUGUGACUUCUUGGAUUGCUUGCCCCUUUCCUGGAAAACUCAUGAAUAAUCUACCCCUUAUUUAGCAUGUAAUCAAGAAAUAACUAUAAGUAUACUCAGUUGAGCAGCCCAUGCUCCUGCUCUGCCUGUGGAGUAGCCAUUUUUUAAUUCUUUACUUCCUUAAUAAACUUGCUUUCACUUUACGAAUUCACCUCAAAUUCUUUCUUGUGUGAGACCCAAGAACCCUCUCCUGGGGUCUGGAUCGGGAUCCCUUUUCAGUAACACUCCAAGCCCCCAUUCUUUCUGUAACCUCAGAAAAAGCUUCACCCAUCUGGCCAUUUCUUUAAGUUCUUUUGUUUUGUGAGACUUCUGUUCAUAUUAAUAUAUUUGCUUUUUCUCCUAUUAAUCUGCCUUUAGUUGAUUUUUCAUCGAGCUUGGAGAGUGAAGAGGAAGUUUUCCCAUGGCUCCUGCAAUAGCAUGGAAUAGGGAAGCUCACUGAGGAGCAUCAGAGGUUAGAUUAGAUUGCAUGAAAUUGCUGCUUUUUUAGGUCAAAAAUAGAGAACCAUUGGUGGUUUCAUAUGGUUCAACCUAUUCUAUGGAUUCCCUUAUGGGAAUGGCUGUGUUCUUCCUUCAGCAGACACUUGCUUAUCCUGUAGGAAAUGCCCUGCCUCCCUCCUCUGUUCUUCUUCUCUUUUGGAAAAUAUGUACUGGGAGCUUUUUAAGUACAGAGCAUGUGCUUAGUCCUGGAUAUGUGGUCAUGAACUGGACCUUGCUGGUGUCUAGAGUCUAGACCGGAGUGUUUUGGGGCUAAUGGAAAACUCUGAGGUGUGGUGGUGUGGGGCUGCAAAACAAACACAAACAAAAACAAAAAGUAGCCUUUUUUUUUGAUGCUGGCUUUCCCCAGAUACUAGCAAAUCCAUCCUAACAGUAAGUAGAGAAACGGAGCUUGAUGGAAUAUUUGUGUUCAUUUCAGUGGAAAGAAAAUGUUUGCCUUCACUUUCUCAGAACUUUCUUUUGCGGAGAAAACAGCUGAUGAACCUGCUGGUAAGAACAAAGAGCCAGACCUCUGUUUGUCUGCAAAUCUGGUUUUCACACAGAGCUUCCUGAUGAAGUGUGAGGAGCCUCCUCGCAGUGAUAGACCAGGGAACAGGGGAGAACCUUUCCCCCUCACACUUGGCAUCCCAGCACCUGGCCCCAAGCUCUGUUGCUUGAGAAGAUUGUGCUGCUGAAAGCUCAUUUCUUUUUUUCCUGUCUAAAGGCAAAACAAGGUAAAAUACAAUAGCCAGUUGCCUCAUAUAAACCACCUGCUUAGUAGGAAAUGAAGUAAAACUCUGCAGUCCCUAUUGCUACUUGAAGAAUUUGUGGUUUCCUUUCCUGUCAGUAAACAAAAGCCGUCAGUUAAAAGAGUGGAACAUUAAUUGUUUACAGGAUGUUUGCUGUAACAAAGGAAGGAAAAGUGCCUUUUACAGACUGUUCAUUGUGUUGGGGAUAUUACAACACCAAGUGUCUCUCCUAGAGAAGAGACAUUAAGCAUAAGAUAUUUAGUCACAAAACACAGACUGUUUCAUUAACAGGACUUUAAAAGACUUAUUUUGUAAACUCAAGUUGAGGACUUCAUAACGUAUCGGCAUAAAGAAUAUAGAUGAGAGUAGAAAGCUUCCUUAGAGAAAAAAUGAGAUCCCAAAAUUUUGAAAAAUACUGAUGCUUCAGAGGCUUUGAGGUUUUUUAAAUUGUAGAAUAUCAUGCCUUUUUUUUUUGUAAGAAACAUUUAUCUUUUAUAGUUCAGUAAUGUAUUUUACCUAGGCUUCCGCACGUUGCCUUUCAGUACAGGCAUACUUCGGAGGUUUGCUUAUUUCCCAGACAACUGCAAUAAAACAAAUGUUGCAGUAUAGCAAGUCACACAGAUUUUUUUUUUUUCCAGUGCAUUUAAAAGUUACAGUUACGCUAUACUGGAGUUUAUUAGGUAUGCAGUAGCAUUAUGUCUAAAAAAUGUGCAAACCUUAAUUUAAAAAUACUUUUUGCUAAAAAAUGCAAAUGAUUAUCUGAGCCUUCAGCAAGUCAGUCUUUUUGCGGGUGGAGAAUCUUGCCUCAGUGUUGAUGGCUGUUGACUGAUCAGGGUGGUGGUGGCUGAAGGUUGGGCUGGGUAUGGCAAUUUCUUAAAAUAAGACAACAAUGAAGUUUACCACAUCAAUCGGCUCUUCCUUUCAUGAAAGACUUCAUGCUGUUUCAUAGCAUUUGACCCACAGUAGAACUUCAAGACUGGAGUCUCUCCUCUCAAACCCUGCCAAGUUUAUGUAAUUUCCUAAAUCCUUUGCAACAAUGUUCAUAUCAUCUUCACCUCCAUCUCAAGAAACCAGUUUCUUUGUUCCUCUACAAAAAGCAACUCCUCAUCCAUUCAAGUUUGAUCCUGAGUUUGUAGCAAUUUAGUCAGAUCUUUAGGCGCCAAUUAUAAUUCUAGUUUUCUUGCUAUUUCUUCCUCUAUUGAAAUGUUAAGCCCCCACCCCAAAGUCAUCCUUGAAGGUUGGAGUCAACUUCUUCCAAACUCCUGUUAAUUGUUGAUAUUUUGACCUCCACCCAUGAAUCGUGAAUGUUCUUGAUGGCAUCUAGAAUGGUGAUUUUAAAAGGGUUUCGGUUUACUUUGCCCAGAUCCACCAGAGGAAUUGCUAUCUGUGAUAGCUAUAACAUUAUGAAAAUUACCUCUUAAAUAAUAAAAUUUAAAAGUCAGAUUUACUUUUUAAUCCAUGGGCUGCGGAAUGGAUGUUGUUAGCAGGCAAGAAACAACAUUCAUCUCCUUGUACACCUCUGUCAGAGGUCUCGGAUAACCAGAUGCAUUGUCAAUGAGCAGUAACAUUUUGAAAGGAAUCUUUUUUUCUGAGCACUUGGUUUCAAUGUGGACUUAAAAUAUUUAGUAAAUAAUGCUGUAAACACAUGUGCUGUCAUCCAGGCUUUGUUGUUCCAAUGAUAGAGCACGGGCAGAGUAGAUUUAGCAUAAUUCUUAAGGGCCCAAAGAUUUUUGGAAUGGUAACUAAGCAUGAGUUUCAACUUAAAGUCACCAGCUGCAUUAACUGCUAACAAGAGAAUUAGCCUGUCCUUUAAAGCUUUGAAUCCAGGCAUUGACUUCCCCUCUCUAGCUGUGAAAGCCCUAUAGGACGUCUUCUAAUAGAAGGCUGUUUGAUUUACAUAGAACAUUUGCUGUUUAGUGUAGCUCUCCUUGUACCUCACAAACCAGCCUCUGCUACCUGCAGACUUUUCUUCUGCAGCCUCCUCACCUCUCUCAGCCUUCAUUGAAUUGAAGAGUAUUAGGGCCUUUCUCUGAACUAGGCUUUGGCUUAAGGAAAUGUGGCUGGUUUCAUCUUCUAUCCAGAACACUCAAACUUUCCCCGUAUCAGCAACGAGAUUGUUUUGCUUUCUUAUCAUUUGUGUGUUCACUGAAGUACCACUUUUAAUUUCCUUCAAGAACUUUUCCUUUGUAUUCGCGACUUGGCUGUUUGGCGCAAGAGGCUUAGCUUUCGGCCUGUUUUGGCUUUUGACAUGUCUUCCCCAUUGAGCUUAAUUGCUUCUGGUUUUUUAUUUAAAGUGAGUUGUUUGACUCUUACUUGAAUACGGAGAGGCUGUUGUAUGGUUAUUAAUUGGCCUACGUUCAAUAUUGUUGUGUCUCAGGGAAUCGGGAGGUCUGAGGAGAGAGAGAGAAAUGGGGGAGGCUGGUCGGUGGAGCCAUCAGAACACAAUAUUUAUGGAUUAAAUACACUGUUUUAUAUGAAUGUGGCUCAUGCCACCCUAGAACAGUUACACUAGUUCCAUCCAAGAUCGCUGAUCACAGGUCACCAUAACAAACAUAAAAGUAAUGACGAAGUUCGAAGUAUUGUGAGAAUCACAGUGUGACACAGAAACACCAAAUGAGCACUUAAAAAAUGGUGCCGAUAGACUUGCUCCAUGCAGGGUUGCCACAAACCUCCAGUCUAUAAAAGACACAGUGUCUGCAAAGCACUGUAACAUGAGGUUCACCUUAUACCUAGUACUGUGUCUGAGUCCCUGACGGUACUAGACGUCCACUGAUGUUACGUAGAUUGAGACUGUUGUGCAACCAUCACCAUCAUCCAUUUUCAGACCUCUUCAUCUUGAAAACUCUGUAUCUAUUUAACCCCAUUUCCCCUCACCCCAAUCCCUGGCAGCCACCGUUGUACUUUCUGAUUUUAUGAAUUUGACUUACUCUACAUACCUCAUAUAAAUGGAAUCAUACAGUAUUUGUCCUUUUUGUGACUGGCUUAUUUGCUUAGCGUGGUAUCUUCAGGGUUCUUCUAUGUUGUAGUUUGUGUGAGACUUUGCUUCCUCUUUAAGGCUGAAUAAUAUUCCACGGCACGUAUUUCCCAUAUGUUGUUUUCUGUAUUCAUCUAAUGGGCGUUUGGGUUGCUUCUACCUUUUGGGCCACUGUGAAUAAUGUUGCUGAGAACAGGGCUGUGCCAGUUCAUCUUCGAGAUCCUGCUUUCAGUUCUUUUGGCUGUAUGCCCAGAAGUAGAAUUGCUGGGUUAUAUGGUAAUGCUGUGUUUAAUUUUUUUUUUUAGGUACCCACUAUAUUAUGCAUCAGAUUUUUAAACUCAGAACUGUCUACAUUGGCUACAAAAAUGGUUCUUGCCAGGCUGUGUGAGCAGGAGCCCGCUGCUCUUCCCCACUCAGGUGAAGGAAAUACUCAUGACCAGCCAGAUGUCUUAAGGAAUGCUUUUGAAAAGAACAGAGGCGUACAACAUUAUUACGACAACAGAGAAGCAAGUUGGCUUUGAAGAAACUGUAUUCUGAGGAUGUUGUUUGCUUUGGGCUAAGAAAAGAAAAAAUACAACUACAGACAAAGCCUUUAUAUCUGCAAGUAUUAUGGCGUGGUCGGUAGCAAUGUAAUUAGAUUUACAUCAGUCUUCCUGGUGAGACUUGGAGGCUCUUCCUCGGUAGACAUGAGUGACCCAAGGCAGUCACAAGAAGAGAAGCACAAGCUAGGCAGAGCCUCUUCAAAGUUCAAGGAUCCCCCUAGAAUCAUGCAGUCAGAUGAUUAUUUUGCUCGGAAAUUUAAAGCCAUUAAUGGCAACAUGGGACCCACUACUUCUUUAAAUGCCUCGAAUUCCAAUGAGACUGGCGGUGGUGGUCCGGCUAAUGGUACCCCAGCUGUGCCCAAGAUGGGUGUGAGAGCAAGGGUGUCUGAAUGGCCUCCUAAAAAGGACUGUUCCAAGGAGCUAACAUGCAAGGCACUGUGGGAAAGCCGGUCUCAGACCAGUUAUGAAAGCAUCACUUCUGUCCUGCAGAAUGGGCAGAGUGACCAGAGUGAAGGUCAGCAAGAUGAACAGCUCGAUCUGGACUUCGUGGAGGCCAAGUACACAAUCGGAGACAUCUUUGUCCAUUCCCCCCAAAGAGGACUUCACCCCAUAAGACAGAGGAGCAAUAGUGAUGUCACUAUCAGUGACAUUGAUGCCGAAGAUGUCUUAGACCAAAAUGCAGUCAACCCCAACACCGGGGCUGCCCUGCACAGGGAGUAUGGAAGUACUUCAUCCAUCGACAGGCAAGGCUUAUCUGGUGAAAACUUUUUUGCUAUGCUCAGAGGGUACCGAGUAGAAAAUUAUGACCACAAAGCAAUGGUCCCUUUUGGGUUCCCUGAAUUUUUCCGCUGUGACCCUGCAAUCUCUCCGAGCCUUCAUGCAGCAGCACAGAUUUCUAGGGGAGAAUUUGUCCGCAUCUCAGGAUUAGAUUAUGUGGACAGUGCCCUCCUGAUGGGGAGAGACAGGGACAAGCCUUUCAAACGGAGGUUGAAAUCAGAGUCGGUGGAAACAUCUCUCUUCCGAAAGCUUCGAACUGUUAAAAGUGAGCACGAAACUUUCAAGUUCACGUCUGAGCUGGAGGAGAGCCGACUGGAGAGGGGCAUUCGCCCUUGGAAUUGUCAGCGAUGUUUUGCACAUUAUGAUGUCCAGAGCAUUUUGUUUAAUAUCAACGAAGCCAUGGCUACGAGGGCUAAUGUGGGGAAAAGGAAAAACAUAACCACUGGGGCAUCUGCAGCAUCCCAGACUCAGAUGCCUACGGGCCAGACAGGCAACUGUGAGUCCCCUUUAGGGAGCAAGGAGGACCUCAACUCCAAAGAGAACCUGGAUGCCGAUGAGGGUGAUGGGAAAAGUAACGACCUCGUCCUUAGUUGUCCUUACUUUAGAAAUGAGACUGGAGGGGAAGGCGACAGGCGGAUUGCGCUCUCUCGAGCCAACUCAUCCUCUUUCAGUUCUGGGGAAAGCUGCUCUUUCGAAUCGUCACUCAGCUCUCACUGCACAAAUGCAGGUGUCUCCGUCUUGGAAGUGCCCAGAGAAAACCAGCCUAUUCACAGGGAGAAAGUGAAGCGCUACAUCAUAGAACACAUUGACCUUGGGGCCUAUUAUUACCGCAAAUUCUUCUAUGGGAAAGAGCACCAAAACUACUUUGGAAUAGAUGAAAACCUUGGUCCAGUAGCAGUCAGCAUCCGGAGAGAGAAGGUGGAAGAUGCCAAGGAGAAAGAAGGAUCCCAGUUCAACUACAGGGUGGCUUUCAGGACAAGUGAGCUUACAACACUGAGAGGAGCAAUUUUAGAAGAUGCUAUACCCUCUACUGCUAGGCAUGGUACCGCACGAGGACUACCUCUCAAAGAAGUUUUGGAAUACGUCAUUCCAGAGCUGAGCAUUCAGUGUUUGCGACAGGCUUCCAACUCACCCAAGGUCUCAGAGCAGCUGCUCAAGCUUGAUGAACAAGGGCUGAGCUUUCAGCACAAGAUCGGGAUCCUUUAUUGCAAAGCAGGCCAGAGCACAGAGGAAGAGAUGUAUAACAAUGAGACGGCGGGACCAGCUUUUGAAGAAUUCCUUGAUCUUCUGGGCCAGAGAGUCCGACUGAAAGGAUUUAGUAAAUAUCGAGCUCAGCUAGACAAUAAGACUGAUUCCACGGGCACGCACUCUCUCUAUACCACAUACAAAGACUACGAACUCAUGUUCCACGUGUCAACCCUGCUUCCCUACAUGCCCAACAACAGACAACAGCUACUGAGGAAAAGGCACAUAGGAAAUGACAUCGUCACCAUCGUCUUCCAGGAGCCUGGGGCACUUCCUUUUACUCCAAAAAGCAUCCGGUCUCACUUUCAGCAUGUCUUUGUCAUAGUCAAAGUGCAUAAUCCAUGUACCGAAAAUGUGUGUUAUAGUGUUGGAGUUUCCAGAUCAAAAGAUGUGCCACCAUUUGGCCCACCGAUUCCCAAAGGUGUAACUUUUCCAAAGUCAGCCGUGUUCCGGGACUUCCUUUUAGCCAAAGUAAUCAAUGCAGAAAAUGCAGCCCAUAAAUCAGAAAAGUUUCGAGCAAUGGCCACUCGAACGAGGCAGGAGUACUUGAAAGAUCUGGCGGAGAACUUUGUCACAACCGCCACCGUGGAUACCUCUGUGAAGUUCAGCUUCAUUACGCUGGGUGCGAAGAAAAAGGAGAAGGUAAAGCCAAGGAAGGAUGCCCACUUGUUUAGCAUUGGGGCCAUCAUGUGGCACGUGAUAGCCCGGGACUUCGGCCAGUCUGCUGACAUUGAAUGUCUUCUCGGGAUCUCCAAUGAGUUCAUCAUGUUGAUUGAAAAGGAUUCCAAGAAUGUUGUAUUCAACUGUUCCUGCAGGGAUGUGAUUGGGUGGACAUCUGGAUUAGUGAGUAUCAAAGUGUUUUACGAAAGAGGAGAAUGUGUCCUCCUGUCCUCGGUAGACAACUGUGCUGAAGACAUCAGGGAAAUUGUUCAGCGAUUAGUAAUAGUGACGAGAGGCUGCGAGACUGUGGAAAUGACCCUGAGGAGGAACGGGCUGGGCCAGCUUGGCUUCCAUGUGAAUUUUGAAGGAAUUGUCGCAGAUGUGGAACCUUUUGGCUUUGCCUGGAAGGCUGGCCUUCGCCAAGGGAGCCGCCUCGUGGAGAUCUGCAAAGUAGCCGUGGCCACUCUGACCCACGAGCAGAUGAUCGACCUGCUCCGUACUUCUGUGACUGUGAAGGUGGUCAUCAUCCAGCCCCAUGAUGACGGCUCGCCCCGAAGAGGGUGUUCAGAGCUCUGCCGGAUCCCUAUGGUGGAAUAUAAACUCGACAGCGAGGGCACCCCCUGCGAGUAUAAAACCCCCUUCAGGAGGAACACCACGUGGCACCGGGUGCCCACUCCUGCCCUGCAGCCCCUCUCUAGAGCUUCCCCCAUCCCCGGCACGCCCGACCGGCUGCCGUGCCAACAGCUGCUCCAGCAGGCCCAGGCUGCCAUUCCUCGAAGCACCUCCUUCGACCGGAAGCUGCCCGAUGGCACGAGAAGCUCACCCAGCAACCAGUCAUCCUCCAGCGACCCUGGACCCGGCGGGAGCGGACCCUGGAGACCACAAGUGGGCUACGACGGGUGCCAGUCCCCUCUACUGCUCGAACACCAGGGCUCAGGCCCUUUGGAAUGUGACGGAGCCAGGGAGAGGGAAGACACCAUGGAAGCAAGCAGGCACCCGGAAACCAAAUGGCAUGGCCCACCUUCCAAAGUCCUGGGUUCCUAUAAAGAAAGAGCUCUGCAGAAAGAUGGAAGUUGCAAAGAUUCCCCCAAUAAGCUUUCUCACAUUGGGGAUAAAAGUUGCUCCAGUCACUCCAGCAGCAACACGCUCUCCAGCAACACCUCCAGCAACAGUGACGACAAGCACUUUGGGUCUGGCGACCUGAUGGACCCCGAAUUACUGGGGCUGACCUACAUCAAAGGGGCCUCCACCGACAGUGGCAUCGACACGGCCCCCUGCAUGCCUGCCACCAUCCUCGGCCCUGUGCACCUGGCAGGCAGCAGGUCCCUGAUCCACAGCCGGGCCGAGCAGUGGGCUGAUGCUGCCGACGUCUCUGGGCCUGACGACGAGCCAGCCAAGUUAUAUUCUGUGCAUGGCUACGCGUCCACCAUCUCCGCCGGCAGUGCUGCGGAAGGCAGCAUGGGCGAUCUCAGUGAGAUAUCCUCUCAUUCCAGUGGUUCUCACCAUUCAGGAAGCCCUUCAGCUCACUGUUCAAAAAGUAGUGGGUCUCUGGAUUCAUCCAAAGUCUACAUCGUGUCUCACAGCAGCGGACAACAGGUUCCCGGGUCCAUGUCCAAGCCCUACCACAGACAAGGGGCAGUGAACAAAUAUGUCAUCGGCUGGAAGAAAUCGGAGGGCAGCCCACCGCCCGAGGAGCCUGAAGUGACUGAAUGUCCCGGGAUGUAUAGUGAGAUGGAUGUCAUGUCCACAGCAACUCAGCAUCAGACAGUGGUGGGAGAUGCUGUUGCAGAGACUCAACAUGUUCUGUCUAAAGAAGAUUUUCUGAAAUUGAUGCUUCCUGACAGCCCCUUAGUGGAGGAGGGGCGAAGAAAGUUUUCGUUCUAUGGGAACCUGUCUCCAAGGAGGUCGCUUUACCGCACGCUGUCUGACGAGAGCAUCUGCAGCAACAGGAGGGGGUCCUCCUUUGGCAGUUCCCGGAGUUCCGUGCUUGACCAGGCCCUGCCCAACGACAUUCUGUUCAGCACCACCCCACCCUACCACAGCACGCUGCCUCCGCGGGCCCACCCCGCACCCAGCAUGGGGAGCCUGAGAAAUGAGUUCUGGUUCUCCGAUGGGUCCUUAUCAGAUAAGUCCAAGUGCGCAGAUCCUGGCCUGAUGCCCCUCCCGGACACAGCCACAGGGUUAGAUUGGACCCACCUCGUGGAUGCUGCACGGGCAUUUGAAGGUCUUGACUCAGAUGAAGAACUGGGGCUGCUCUGUCACCACACGUCCUAUCUAGACCAGAGGGUGGCAUCCUUCUGCACCCUGACAGAUAUGCAGCAUGGGCAGGACCUGGAAGGGGCCCAAGAGCUGCCCUUAUGUGUAGAUCCAGGCAGUGGCAAAGAGUUCAUGGACACAACUGGGGAGCGUUCUCCAUCACCACUGACCGGGAAAGUCAAUCAGCUGGAAUUAAUUCUUCGACAACUCCAGACCGACCUUCGGAAGGAAAAACAAGACAAGGCCGUUCUCCAAGCAGAAGUGCAGCACCUGAGACAGGACAACAUGAGACUGCAGGAGGAGUCCCAGACCGCGACAGCUCAGCUGCGGAAAUUCACAGAAUGGUUUUUCACCACCAUCGACAAAAAAUCUUAGCCAAUCCGCACCUCAUCAAGGGACCACUGGGAAAUGCCCCUUGUCCCUUUGAAGUCACAAACAUGUGGUUUUUCUGUGUGCUUUCAACCAAUCGUAGAUGUUUUUGCUGUUCCAUUCUGUGUAGCACCAUUCACCACAGCAGGAUAGGGAGCCUCGACUCUUUCUCGGUAACCACGGCAGAGAGCAGCGCCGAUGUGAAGAUGAAUGAAUGUAACUCCUGGUGUGAAGAUGAAUGUAAACCCUGGCGACAGUUGAGACCUUUUUCUUUUAGACUCUGCUAAAACAGUGCUCUGGCUUGGGCUUACCUCAAGAGGGAAGAUAGUUGAGUUUUAUUUCCUGUAUAUCAGGUGACCUGGUAGAGAUGUAAAGCAAUUUACCAUAGUUUGGGCUUUAGUAUUGUAAAAUAAACAUGAGAACAAAUAAUCAGACAUAUACUUUAAUGUUAAAGGUGCUCUAUUUUUUUGGAUGUACAGUAGUUUUAUUUCCACAGCCACAUUACCAUAGCAAUAAGAAAGGAGGCAUAGUACAUAGUUGGAAAAGCUUUGUGGGGGGAUUAAAAAAAAAAAAAAGCACUGUUGUGUUUAACACUAGUUCAGAUGCAGUUACCUUAGAGACUUAUUUAUUUGCAGGAACAAAUGGUGCCUGAAUAUUAACAGUGUUCUGAUUAAAAACAAAAAAAAGAUACAUAUGCCUUGUAAAUGGCUCACCGAGUGGUCAGUAGUCACUUCAACUCUUAGUUCACUUUUGUAUAGUUGCUCUGCUGGAAAGAAAUGAGAGUGAAUCUGCUUACUCACUAGAACUUCCCUGUGUGCUGUGAGCCAGCGGAACCACUUGUACAAUGCCAGAUUUGUUUAUCUUUGUACAGAAGCUUUGAUGAAGUGUCUUGUAUUUAACACCCUUAUUUAAGCUUAUUUAACCUUAAAUUGUUAAUUUUAUAAAAUUUGGUUUGGCCUGCACUACGAUGAGGGAUGGAGGUAGCUGCAGGCUCAGAAGAGACUGAGCUUGCACAGAUCAGACCGAGAAGCAGGGUGAGAGAUUCUAACGACUGGAUGCUGCUAGUAACACAUUGUUUGUAUUGCUUUACCAUUUUUAACUGUUAGAUUUGAGAUGAACAUACAUUUUGCUUUUUUAAUAAAUGUUUAAAAGAAGUCCACAUAAGAAA